GAGCAAGAGGAAGAUGGCCGUGCCCUGUUUUUCGGUGUAAGGCAGCGACGGCGGCUGCGACGGCGAGACUGAGAUCCUGGUGUCGUGGGCACCUGAGUUCUAGCUUCCCCCAGCGAGCGCGCGUCCCUUCGUGCCUAGGCGAGAGCCGGCUCUUCCCCGGGAGAUGCGUUUGUCCCAGGCUCGGGGGCUCAGUGGGAGUUCAUGCUGCGCUGGAGGCUCUUGGCCACCGCUCUAAUCGCCUUGUGCCGCCGCAGCGCCAGCUCCGUCGCCAGCGGUGAGCCUCCCGAUUCCCCCCCUUGCCCCUGGCGGCGGCGAUGACCGGGGAGAAGAUCCGCUCACUGCGGAGGGACCACAAGCCCAGCAAAGAAGAAGGGGACCUGCUGGAGCCCGGGGAUGAGGAAGCGGCGGCUGCCCUCGGCGGUACCUUUACCAGAAGCAGGAUUGGCAAGGGCGGCAAAGCUUGUCAUAAGAUCUUCAGUAACCAUCACCACCGGCUACAGCUGAAGGCAGCUCCGGCCUCCUCCAAUCCCCCCGGCGCCCCGGCUCUGCCGCUGCACAAUUCCUCCGUGACUGCCAACUCCCAGUCCCCGGCCCUUCUGGCCGGCACCAACCCCGUUGCUGUCGUCGCGGAUGGAGGCAGUUGCCCCGCACACUACCCGGUGCACGAGUGCGUCUUCAAGGGGGAUGUGAGGAGACUCUCCUCUCUCAUCCGCACGCACAAUAUCGGGCAGAAAGAUAAUCACGGAAAUACUCCUUUACACCUUGCUGUGAUGUUAGGAAAUAAAGAAUGUGCCCAUUUACUUUUGGCUCACAAUGCUCCAGUCAAGGUGAAAAAUGCUCAGGGAUGGAGCCCUCUGGCGGAAGCCAUCAGCUAUGGAGAUAGGCAGAUGAUUACAGCUCUUUUGAGGAAGCUUAAGCAGCAAUCCAGGGAAAGUGUUGAAGAAAAACGACCUCGAUUAUUAAAAGCCCUGAAAGAGCUAGGUGACUUUUAUCUAGAACUUCACUGGGAUUUUCAAAGCUGGGUGCCUUUACUUUCCCGAAUUCUGCCUUCCGAUGCAUGUAAAAUAUACAAACAAGGUAUCAAUAUCAGGCUUGACACAACUCUCAUAGACUUUACUGACAUGAAGUGCCAACGAGGGGAUCUAAGCUUCAUUUUCAAUGGGGAUGCGGCGCCCUCUGAAUCUUUUGUAGUAUUAGACAAUGAACAAAAAGUUUAUCAGCGAAUACAUCAUGAGGAAUCAGAGAUGGAAACAGAAGAAGAGGUGGAUAUUUUAAUGAGCAGUGAUAUUUACUCUGCAACUUUAUCAACAAAAUCAAUUUCUUUCACGCGUGCCCAGACAGGAUGGCUUUUUCGGGAAGAUAAAACAGAAAGAGUAGGAAACUUUUUGGCAGACUUUUACCUGGUGAAUGGACUUGUUUUAGAAUCAAGGAAAAGAAGAGAACAUCUCAGUGAAGAGGAUAUUCUUCGAAAUAAGGCCAUCAUGGAGAGUUUGAGUAAAGGUGGAAACAUAAUGGAACAGAAUUUUGAGCCGAUUCGAAGACAGUCUCUUACACCUCCUCCUCAGAACACUAUUACAUGGGAAGAAUAUAUAUCUGCUGAAAAUGGAAAAGCUCCUCAUCUGGGUAGAGAAUUGGUGUGCAAAGAGAGUAAGAAAACGUUUAAAGCUACGAUAGCCAUGAGCCAGGAAUUUCCCUUAGGGAUAGAGUUAUUAUUGAAUGUUUUAGAAGUAGUAGCUCCCUUCAAGCACUUUAACAAGCUUAGAGAAUUUGUUCAGAUGAAGCUUCCUCCAGGCUUUCCUGUAAAAUUAGAUAUACCUGUGUUUCCCACAAUCACAGCCACUGUGACUUUUCAGGAGUUUCGAUACGAUGAAUUUGAUGGCUCCAUCUUUACUAUACCUGAUGACUACAAGGAAGACCCAAGCCGUUUUCCUGAUCUUUAACUGACGUGGAAAAGGAUGCCGUCUAACCAAGGAAAGAAAAUACAGAGACCCUAGAAGUGGAUCCAAAUAGAAGGGACAAAUGCUUUCAGUGAAGAAAAGGGAAUUACACAUUGAAUCGACACAUCAGUAAUACGAUACAGUGAAAUGGGCCUCUAAUAAGAAUUUCAGCGAGUUUUCUGAUGUGCCAUUUUUUGUCUUUUUAAAAAUAUACAUAUUAUAAAUGUAAUAGUUUGACACAUUAAUGACCCUAAGACCUGCGUAUGUGAAGCAGCUAUGAGUGCUGUGAUUUGUUUUUAAAAAUUUUUACACUUCUUGUUGAAAUAUAUAUGCAUAUAAAUAUAUCUAUAUCUAUAUCUAUAUCUAAAACACUCCUGGACCAUUAACGUAAAUUAAAUGUCUUAAGAGAUAUGGAGCCCUUUUAAACUUGUCAUCUUUAUGCAAGGUGACAUUUAUAAAUAUUCCUUCGAGCUUUGUUUUCAUAAAAUGUAAACUAUGUAACAUUAUGUAUAGUUCAGUAAUUUGAAUGUUUGUUCAAUAUAAUGAACUAGAAGGAAUGCAAUUUUCUGUAGAUGAAUGAACCAAAUGGUAACCAUUAAACAAUUGCAUUUAUAUGUUGCAAUACAUUUCAGAAGGAGCGUUCACUCUGCAGGGAAUAAGGUACCUCCUUUAGCACCUUAGUGCAAUUCAUUGUGGUGCUAUUUGUUUUUACCUGAAUGUUUGUUACUAAUCUUCCUUUCAUAGAACCUCUAUUUUUUUUUUUUCUAAACUUGAGUUUGAGUCCUUGUUAUGGUCAUCAUAAGGUAAUGGUUAGCAUGUUUAAAGAUAUUCCUCUUCCAAAUCUCAGCACUUUAAAAAAAAAUCCAAAUUUUUAAACUUGCUUCCUAAUAAGUACACAUCGGUCUGAUUAUUUUGUUUGUUUUUAGUAGAAUAUGGAUGCAUUGGUGUCAGUUUUAAAAAACAAUACACAUAUUUUGGACAACCCUACAUAUUUAAUCCUUUCAAAAUAAGAUAAAAACAUUUUAUAUGCUAACAGAAUAUAUUUGUUACAAGUUAAAGUCCAGAAGUAUACACAAGAUUGAUUACUCCUAUUAUUUUUUUUAAAUCACAGGAAAAUAUUGAUUUCAUUGUCUCCAAAGUGAUAAAAUCAUGUAUUACUCAUUUUUGCACUUAAAAUUUUUCUUAUUUAUUCCAAGGUGGUUUGAAGGUCCAAGUAUGAAAAUAAAUUAGGGGGAUUAAUGUAUAACAGUUAUAAAGUAUCAUGUUGUAUUAAAGAGCUUACUUAGAUUGAUGUUUUUAAAAUGUAUCCUGAUGAAUGUCUCAAGAAUGCAUCUGUCAAGUUUUUUAGACUGACCAGUAGCUUAAACUUUUUUCAGGAUUUUAGGUAAUUUGAAAGGAGUUUAGAGACCCUUAUUGAAAAUAUGAUUUAAAAAUCCAAAGCAUAAACCGUAAGAAAAAUUUUAAAUAAACAUCUUUAAAGCUGCAUCUUCCAUACUGAUACAUGCAUUGCGUAUGUUGACAUUAAAUACAUUUUAUAAUGAAGAAAAAUAAUCAUAGUAAAAAAUUGAAAGACCUAAUUACUACGUUACAUGGACCUAUUGAAUUUUGGGGGAACGUGUUAGUAAACCCAGACUAGCUUUGUUGAAUAGAAGUUGAUCGCUGUUAUUUAGGAAAUGGGUAGAUCAAAUGACUUAGAGACUGAAUUAUCCUAUCAGUGGUUACAUGGGGUUGGAGACACUGAAAGGCAGUGAUCACUGUUGCUUCUAGGCUCCCUUACUUUGUAGGAAUAUGGUAUACUUUCAGGAAUAUGCUAUAUAUGUUUUCAUAAGUACAGACACCUUAGGGAAGAAAAAAAGUGGGUAAUUGAAGCUUAUGGUUGAUUAAUUUCCUAACAGCACAGCUAUGAAUAUUUUGCUGGGGUACACUGGAGGUAGGAAGACUACUGGAAAUUUUUGCACUUGAAUUUUGUUUUUAAAGCUUUUUUCUUUAAAGAAUGGUAGAAACAGAUUAUCCAUUCCAAAAUGUCUUUUCUCUGAUCACAAAGAGCAAACAAAUGUCAAUAUCUCUUAUGAUGGUGAAAAAAAGGAAUUAAUCGAUGCAAAUAAACUUUUCACAGUAUUACUUUUAAUGAAGAUUUUUCGAAAUGUGCCUUUUAAUCCAGUUAAUGAAUGAAGCUAUAUGCAGUGUUUCAAAUGAAUAAGUCAAAACACCAUAUGUUUUCAUAAUACCACAUGAAAAAUCAAGAUUUUGCAAUGUAGGUACACAAAAUUCUAUAUGUUCUUCUCCAUUUGUGAUUUUGAAACUGUUUAAAUUGGUAGGGGGACAAUCGUAUAGUCAUCUUCAAUAGCCAUUUAGAAAUGGUUAAUAUUCUUGCCCACUGGUAUGGUAUCCAGAGAAGAUAUGGUUUCCAUCUUUGAGAAAAUAAUUCUCUGAUGAGACAAUUUGCCCUCUGUAGAUAUUCACAUACAGAGAAUUGCCAAACUUCAUAAAAGGGUAGUAUGAAGUAGAUGCCCUGAUUUUUGUGAGUAUAAGAAGUACAGAUGAUGGUUUGGAAACUGUCACAUCUGUCUGCUGAUACAUGUUAGUAGAUGAAAAACUGUUUCCUUCUGCUCAGAACUGGAAUUAAGCCCCACUCAUGCUAAUAAAAAUGGGUUUUUAUAGUAGUAUUCACAUACAGUUUAUUAUUCACACACUGGGGGAGGGUGAUGAAUAAUGAUUAUUUAAUGAGCCCUCUUCCUAGUUUUCCCUAAGUCUGCAGAAGACAAAGAUCCUGUUUCCAGGCCAUGAAAGGACUGAAGUAAAUAUUGUAAAUAAGUACAGCUGACCCUUGAACAACAUGGAGGUUAGGGGUUCAGUUGAAAAUCUGCAUGUAAGUGGACCUGUGCAGUCCAAACCUGUGUUUAACUGCUGAAUUAAAGGUGCUUCCUUCUGCUCAUUGAUAUUACCCAUAUUUACAAACAUGCUAGAGAAAAGCAACUGGUGUAAAACUUGCCCCCACUAGAGAAAUGGACAGGAGGUAUUAAGUCACUUGUAAAGAUAGAUAGCAGAACUAAGCUUGGUAAAAGCCCAUGAUUGUUUGUAUACUAUAAAUUAGCCAAAACUACUCUUGCAAAGCAUUUUAUGUCAGAAAUCUGGGGCAAUAGUAACUAACUCUGGUUGCCACCUAAAAAUUUCAUAACAUGUUAAGAAUCACAUUUUUUACAUCAUGCAAACCAUCCUUACAGAGUGAGCUUACCUUGUGAUGAGCUUUUUAAUUGUUACAGUUCAUUUUAGAAGAGUAAUACUUUCAGUCAUAAUGGUACCUAUGGUACAUAGAAUUACAAUUUUGCUUUUUCCACACACUGAAAAAUAUUGAAGCAAAAUCUUAAGAACUUCUAAGAAAGGUGCUUGUUAAUCAUUCUUGGUUUUCAUCAUGUUUUGCGGUGAAAAUGACUUUAAUUAGAGUAGAAAUAUUGUCUAACAUAAAACCAAAAAGAUAAAACCCACCACUUAUUUACCUGUACCUCCCAUACAUAGAGUUCUUGAUGACUAAAGAAGGAUGACAGUAAUUGGGAUGUUCUAAAUACAGUUGUGUGUCACUUAAUGAUGGGUACAUGUUCUGUGGAAUGCAUCAGGUGAUUUUGUCAUUGUGAGAACCAUAUUGGGUGUACUUACACAAACCUAGGUGGUAUAGCAUACCACUCACCUAGACUAUACAAUAAAGCCUAUUGCUCCGAGACCA